AGCCUUGGCCCGGCCGUUGCAGCUGGAACAUCGUGGGGGAGAUGGGAAGAGGAACGGGGCCCGGAGCCCGGGGCUGGGUCCUGGGAAUCCCAUUCCCGCAGCUGGGACUCCAGCUCCCCUGCCAGUUCCUCCAGGCGGAAGCCCUCAGGCUUGGUCCUCACUCCAGCCUCCCGGCCUGGACAGGAAUUCUCUCUCCAGCAGCCCUGCCAGAUGCCCGCCCAGCCCCUGCCUCAGGCGGGGAGGGCUUCAGGGAAGCUCACCAAGGCAGAAGGGCGGGAGAGAUUGUCAGAGCCCCAGCUGGUGUCCAGGGACUGACCGUGAGCCUGGGUGAAAGUGAGUUCCCCGUUGGAGGCAACAGACGAGGAGAGGAUGGAAGGCCUGGCCCCCAAGAAUGAGCCCUGAGGUUCAGGGAGCGGCUGGAGUGAGCCGGCCCCAGAUCUCCGUCCAGCUGCGGGUCCCAGAGGCCUGGGUUACACUCGCAGCUCCUGGGGGAGGCCCUUGACGUGCCUCAGUUCCCAAACAGGAACCCUGGGAAGGACCAGAGAAGUGCCUAUUGCGCAGUGAGUGCCCGACACAGCUGCAUGUGGCCGGUAUCACAGGGCCCUGGGUAAACUGAGGCAGGCGACACAGCUGCAUGUGGCCGGUAUCACAGGGCCCUGGGUAAACUGAGGCAGGCGACACAGCUGCAUGUGGCCGGUAUCACAGGGCCCUGGGUAAACUGAGGCAGGCGACACAGCUGCAUGUGGCCGUAUCACAGGGCCCUGGGUAAACUGAGGCAGGUGACACAGCUGCAUGUGGCCGUAUCACGGGGCCCUGGGUAAACUGAGGCAGGUGACACAGCUGCAUGUGGCCGGUAUCACGGGGCCCUGGAUAAACAGAGGCAGGCGACACAGCUGCAUGUGGCCGGUAUCACAGGGCCCUGGGUAAACUGAGGCAGGCGAGGCCACCCCCAUCAAGUCCCUCAGGUCUAGGUUUGGCAGGUUUGGCAAAAACACAGCAACGCUCGGUUAAAUCUGAAUUUCGGGGGAGAGGAAGUGGAGGGCGCUGGCCGGCCGUGGGGCAAUGCAACGGCCUCCCAGCACAGGGCUAUAAGAGGAGCCGGGCGGGCACGGAGGGGCAGAGACCCCGGAGCCCCAGCCCCACCAUGACCCUCGGCCGCCGACUCGCGUGUCUUUUCCUCGCCUGUGUCCUGCCGGCCUUGCUGCUGGGGGGCACCGCGCUGGCCUCGGAGAUUGUGGGGGGCCGGCGAGCGCGGCCCCACGCGUGGCCCUUCAUGGUGUCCCUGCAGCUGCGCGGAGGCCACUUCUGCGGCGCCACCCUGAUUGCGCCCAACUUCGUCAUGUCGGCCGCGCACUGCGUGGCGAAUGUAAACGUCCGCGCGGUGCGGGUGGUCCUGGGAGCCCAUAACCUCUCGCGGCGGGAGCCCACCCGGCAGGUGUUCGCCGUGCAGCGCAUCUUCGAAAACGGCUACGACCCCGUAAACUUGCUCAACGACAUCGUGAUUCUCCAGCUCAACGGGUCGGCCACCAUCAACGCCAACGUGCAGGUGGCCCAGCUGCCGGCUCAGGGACGCCGCCUGGGCAACGGGGUGCAGUGCCUGGCCAUGGGCUGGGGCCUUCUGGGCAGGAACCGUGGGAUCGCCAGCGUCCUGCAGGAGCUCAACGUGACGGUGGUGACGUCCCUCUGCCGUCGCAGCAACGUCUGCACUCUCGUGAGGGGCCGGCAGGCCGGCGUCUGUUUCGGGGACUCCGGCAGCCCCUUGGUCUGCAACGGGCUAAUCCACGGAAUUGCCUCCUUCGUCCGGGGAGGCUGCGCCUCAGGGCUCUACCCCGAUGCCUUUGCCCCGGUGGCACAGUUUGUAAACUGGAUCGACUCUAUCAUCCAACGCUCCGAGGACAACCCCUGUCCCCACCCCCGGGACCCGGACCCGGCCAGCAGGACCCACUGAGAAGGGCUGCCCGGGUCACCUCAGCUGCCCACACCCACACUCUCCAGCAUCUGGCACAAUAAACAUUCUCUGUUUUGUA